AGUCCCGCCCCCCUCUCCUCGCUGCUUAGGCUCCGCGGCCUCCAAGCUGUAGCUAUGACGGCGCGCGGGACUCCGAGCCGCUUCUUGGCCAGCGUUCUCCACAACGGACUGGGUCGCUAUGUGCAGCAGCUGCAGCGUCUGAGCUUCAGCGUCAGCCGCGACGGCGCCUCGUCUCGCGGCGCCAGGGAGUUCGUGGAGCGGGAGGUGAUCGACUUCGCCCGACGGAAUCCAGGGGUCGUAAUAUAUGUAAACUCGCGUCCGUGCUGCGUGCCCAGAGUAGUGGCCGAAUACCUUAACGGGGCUGUGCGCGAGGAGAGCAUCCACUGCAAGUCGGUCGAGGAGAUCUCGACGCUGGUGCAGAAGCUGGCCGACCAGUCGGGCUUGGACGUGAUCCGCAUCCGCAAGCCCUUCCACACCGACAACCCUAGCAUCCAGGGCCAGUGGCACCCCUUCACCAACAAGCCGACCACGUUCCGCGGGCUACGCCCCCGAGAGGUUCAGGAUCCUGCCCCAGCCCAGGAUGCGGCUGAGUUCCUCGGCGAAGGAGCAGGGCCCUGCUGGUACUCCAUUGUUGCUCUGCCUCAGAAGCACAUAGCUAUUGCCAUUCAUCCUCCGCAGCCGGCUGGGCAGUGCCACCAAGCCAUUGGACACUGGCCUGAGACUGUCUGCAGUUGCACCGCAGAUCCUCCUGCCCGGCUGGCCCGACCCACCAGACCUCCCCACAGUGGAUCCUAUCUCAUCCUCAUUGACCUCUGCUCCAGCCCCUAUGCUGUCCGCAGUUUCUUGCCUCCCGAUUGUCCCUGCACUGACCACUGUGUGCUCAGCGUGAAGGCUGCAUAGAAGUGUGUACGGCUUGAGGUUUCAGCAUCCAGGCUGCAGACCCCACGCAGUGUCUCAUACAGUGGAAUGUGGCAGAUGAGACGGGCUUUCAGGAAGGAAGUCCACUUCUUCUGCAGGAUCUUCUUCCCUCCCAGGUCUCCCUGGGGAGGUAGAGGCACGGGAUAAGGGGCCAGGGUCAGAGGUCCAGCCUCUAUACCCGUGCCCCAACGUCAGCCCAAUCCACCUUGCAGACACGAGCCACACGGGCCACACGGUGACUGCUGCGGCUCUGAGUGAAGCUGCCAGAGCCCUCCUCAGUGGCACGCUCCGUGAAGAAGUAGUACACCUUGUCAUCAUCACCCACUGCACUGGCCUUGCUCUCCCGCACGAGGACGGAGAACACAAACUCCGCAUCUGUGGGUCAGGCAGUUUGAGAGGCUUUUGAGACAGGCUGGGGAUUCCUUUCCCUCACUCUGAGGCUGACCCCUCACUUGACAACACACAGGAAUGGAAUGGACAGGCUCACCUGGGGAUUUGGGGGUGGGGUGGUCAGCUGGCCAAGGGAGUAAAAAUGAAGAAAUAGUCCCCUACCCCCCAUCAUCCUGUGCCUCAUCCUCCUAACCAUUGAGCCAAUGCAUUGGUGUCUCCUCAGUUCUCAGGGAGUGUGGGUGGCGGCUCCGGCGGAUGUCAGGAAUGCUCCGGAAUUCAUACCUAGUGGCUGUGUAGAGGCCUCCAUCUGGCGUGGGGAUAUUCCAGGCAUGAGAGACAUGUCAUAUUCAACAGGGCACAUGACAUAUACAUGGUGGCAGGUCCUAGAGAUGAGAUCCACAUCCUAAAAAUACCAUGUCUGUGAUAGGGAAGAAGGCCUGCUCACCAAUGAUGAGGCCUGUGAAGCCACGGGCUGGGUCAUAAGGACACUUCUCCUUCCCCUCCUCGAAGCUGGUUGGCAAGGUGAAGGCCUCAGCAUCCUAGGGAACAAGGAACCAGCAGUAAGUGGUUCCGAAGACAGGCAGGGACAGUGGCUCAAAGUCAGAUCAGUCUGGGGUCAGGGAUCAGCGAUCAGGGAUAGGGGCAGGUUGUAUGGCAGAUGCACCUGACAGCAAUAACUUAAGCAUCCCCUGAGAAUGACCUUAUGGCCUCAAAACAAUGUAUGUUUGGAGUUCCAAAUCUGCAAGUGGCCAACCUAGAGAUUCACUCCUUAUCUAUGAAGAACAUCUGAGCCCCUAGCCCAUCCUGUGGAACACAUGCUGUCCAGGGGAUCAAGGCCCUUUGUUUUGGGUUAAAUGAAGUUUGCCAGGUGGAGGUGAUUAGGGGGAGGAUGCUAAGUGAAAAUGCUAUAAAAACUGCAUGGUUUUUACAAAGGGGAAUGGUUCUCCAGUGCAGCCCGCCGCCACUGGAGUGCCCUGUAUGGAAGUCCCCUUAAUAAACCAUCCGUCUCCUUCA